GGGAUCCCCUUCGGUCCUCCGGAUGGAGUUGCCGGGUCCGCCUCGCUGGGGUCGGCCCCCUCCCUUCGGGGGCGAGGCUCCAUCUCUUGGGGACUACACCCCCCUUCCCCCCAACUGGGUCUUAGUCCUUUAAAUUCUUGGAAUCACUUUUGGGGCGCUAGAGACCCUGGAGCCGCACAGCGGGGUCCUGGGGGGCUAUAGAGUGGGGUCCUCUGGGCACUUAAUGGGAUUUGGGGGGUUCUGUUGAAAUAUUGCUGGGAGCUCAACUGGAAUGUAAAAGUUCUUCGGGAAGGUGAAGGUCAGGCACGCCGAGGGGGAGAAGCGAGCGGACAUCCAGCUGAACAGCUUCGGUUUCUACACCAAUGGCUCUCUGGAGGUGGAGUUGAGCGUCCUGCGGCUGGGCCUCCGGGAGGCAGAAGAGAAGUCCCUGCUGGUGGGGUUCAGUCUCAGCCGGGUUCGGUCUGGCAGAGUUCGCUCCUAUUCAACCCGGGAUUUCCAGGACUGCCCUCUCCAGAAAAACAGUAGCAGUUUCCUGGUCCUGUUCCUCAUCAACACCAAGGAUCUGCAGUGAGUUGGGGACCGGGGGCUCGCUCAGAUCCUUCGUCUGCGUUUCCCUGGUGUGAUGCCCACACGCACCUGGGCUGAUCAGGGUCCAGGUGCGGAAGUAUGGAGAGCAGAAGACGUUGUUUAUCUUUCCCGGGCUCCUCCCGGAAGCACCCUCCAAACCAGGGCUCCCGAAGCCACAGGCCACAGUCCCCCGCAAGGUGGAUGGCGGAGGGACCUCUGCAGCCAGCAAGCCCAAGUCAACACCCGCAGUGAUUCAGGGUCCUAGUGGGAAGGACAAGGACCUGGUGUUGGGCCUGAGCCACCUCAACAACUCCUACAACUUCAGUUUCCACGUGGUGAUCGGCUCUCAGGCGGAAGAAGGCCAGUACAGCCUGAACUUCCACAACUGCAACAAUUCAGUGCCAGGAAAGGAGCAUCCAUUCGACAUCACGGUGAUGAUCCGGGAGAAGAACCCCGAUGGCUUCCUGUCGGCAGCGGAGAUGCCCCUUUUCAAGCUCUACAUGGUCAUGUCCGCCUGCUUCCUGGCCGCUGGCAUCUUCUGGGUGUCCAUCCUCUGCAGGAACACGUACAGCGUCUUCAAGAUCCACUGGCUCAUGGCGGCCUUGGCCUUCACCAAGAGCAUCUCUCUCCUCUUCCACAGCAUCAACUACUACUUCAUCAACAGCCAGGGCCACCCCAUCGAAGGCCUUGCCGUCAUGUACUACAUCGCACACCUGCUGAAGGGCGCCCUCCUCUUCAUCACCAUCGCCCUGAUUGGCUCAGGCUGGGCCUUCAUCAAGUACGUCCUGUCGGAUAAGGAGAAGAAGGUCUUUGGGAUCGUGAUCCCCAUGCAGGUCCUGGCCAACGUGGCCUACAUCAUCAUCGAGUCCCGCGAGGAAGGCGCCAGCGACUACGUGCUGUGGAAGGAGAUUUUGUUCCUGGUGGACCUCAUCUGCUGUGGUGCCAUCCUGUUCCCCGUAGUCUGGUCCAUCCGGCAUCUCCAGGAUGCGUCUGGCACAGACGGGAAGGUGGCAGUGAACCUGGCCAAGCUGAAGCUGUUCCGGCAUUACUAUGUCAUGGUCAUCUGCUACGUCUACUUCACCCGCAUCAUCGCCAUCCUGCUGCAGGUGGCUGUGCCCUUUCAGUGGCAGUGGCUGUACCAGCUCUUGGUGGAGGGCUCCACCCUGGCCUUCUUCGUGCUCACGGGCUACAAGUUCCAGCCCACAGGAAACAACCCGUACCUGCAGCUGCCCCAGGAGGACGAGGAGGAUGUUCAGAUGGAGCAAGUAAUGACGGACUCUGGGUUCCGGGAAGGCCUCUCCAAAGUCAACAAAACAGCCAGCGGGCGGGAACUGUUAUGAUCACCUCCACAUCUCAGACCAAAGGGUCGUCCUCCCCCAGCAUUUCUCACUCCUGCCCUUCUUCCACAGCGUAUGUGGGGAGGUGGAGGGGGUCCAUGUGGACCAGGCGCCCAGCUCCCCGGGACCCCGGUUCCCGGACAAGCCCAUUUGGAAGAAGAGUCCCUUCCUCCCCCCAAAUAUUGGGCAGCCCUGUCCUUACCCCGGGACCACCCCUCCCUUCCAGCUAUGUGUACAAUAAUGACCAAUCUGUUUGGCUACGCCGUUGUCUUGCCUUUUUGGGGGUUGGGGUCUACACGGAGGUUGUGUUUACAAUGUAGAAACCUGUUUUCGCUGUGUGUGGCGGGGGCGCGGGCACAGGGUCCGUGUCUUUGUAUAUUCAAUAAAUAUUCAUUCAGUAA